GGCUGGCCCCUGAGCCUAUUUUUGUGAAAGGAGCUUUAGCUUACAGAAAGUGGUGAGAGGCCAGUGGGUGUCUGGGGCUGCCCUGUACAGCUCUAGCCCCCUGGGGCCCAUCUCCGUUCCUCCCUCCAGCACUGCCUGAGGGCUCCCAGCCUCCUCGUUCCUUCAGGAGCUCUAUGGACCCCUGGAAGGGAGCAGGGGCAGGUUGUGCUGGCCCCGGGCCCCUCCCCAGUUUCACUUGGCGAGGCUGAUAAGCCAAAUUCCUCUUUGAGAAGUGACGCUGGCUCACCGCAGAGUUGACACACCUUCCUGUGUUGGGGGGGGGGCCUGGCGGGGGUUUCCCAGGGCUAGAAACUGAGAAUGCCCCCCUCCCCGACUGGGGCUGCCCGAGGGUGAUUCCUGAAGCCUGAGUGGGUGGGUGUGCACACAUGUGCACGGCAUAUGCAUGUGUGCACCUGUUUCCAGGGAGGGCAGUUCCGGCCCCAGCCCUGUCCUUACCUCAGCAUCCGGGGAACCUACUACCGACCUGCCCGCUGCCCUGGGCUCAUCCAGCCGGUGGCACAGCUAAGGCUGUCCCAGAGCUCUGCAGGCCGAGCCCCAGCCUGCACAUGGGGGCUGGAGAUGCAGUGGUCCAGCAGGAGGCUCUGCAGGCACCACCAGGGCCUGCACCCAGAGAGGGUGAGCUACGUCCUUGGGGCCACAGGGCACAACUUCACCCUCCACCUGCGGAAGAACAGGGACCUGCUGGGCUCCGGCUACACAGAGACCUAUACGGCUGCCAAUGGCUCCGAGGUGACGGAGCAGCCUCGCGGGCAGGACCACUGCUUCUACCAGGGCCACGUAGAGGGGUACCCGGACUCAGCCGCCAGCCUCAGCACCUGUGCCGGCCUCAGGGGUUUCUUCCAGGUGGGGUCAGACCUGCACCUGAUCGAGCCCCUGGAUGAAGGUGGCGAGGGCGGACGGCACGCCGUGUACCAGGCUGAGCACCUGCUGCAGACGGCCGGGACCUGCGGGGUCAGCGACGACAGCCUGGGCAGCCUCCUGGGACCCCGGACGGCAGCCGUCUUCAGGCCUCGGCCCGGGGACUCUCUGCCAUCCCGAGAGACCCGCUACGUGGAGCUGUAUGUGGUCGUGGACAAUGCAGAGUUCCAGAUGCUGGGGAGCGAAGCAGCCGUGCGUCAUCGGGUGCUGGAGGUGGUGAAUCACGUGGACAAGCUAUAUCAGAAACUCAACUUCCGUGUGGUCCUGGUGGGCCUGGAGAUUUGGAAUAGUCAGGACAGGUUCCACGUCAGCCCCGACCCCAGUGUCACACUGGAGAACCUCCUGACCUGGCAGGCACGGCAACGGACACGGCGGCACCUGCAUGACAACGUACAGCUCAUCACGGGUGUCGACUUCACCGGGACUACCGUGGGGUUUGCCAGGGUGUCCGCCAUGUGCUCCCACAGCUCAGGGGCUGUGAACCAGGACCACAGCAAGAACCCCGUGGGCGUGGCCUGUACCAUGGCCCAUGAGAUGGGCCACAACCUGGGCAUGGACCAUGAUGAGAACGUCCAGGGCUGCCGCUGCCAGGAACGCUUCGAGGCCGGCCGCUGCAUCAUGGCGGGCAGCAUUGGCUCCAGUUUCCCCAGGAUGUUCAGUGACUGCAGCCAGGCCUACCUGGAGAGCUUUUUGGAGCGGCCGCAGUCGGUGUGCCUCGCCAACGCCCCUGACCUCAGCCACCUGGUGGGCGGCCCCGUGUGUGGGAACCUGUUUGUGGAGCGUGGGGAGCAGUGCGACUGCGGCCCCCCCGAGGACUGCCGGAACCGCUGCUGCAACUCUACCACCUGCCAGCUGGCUGAGGGGGCCCAGUGUGCGCACGGUACCUGCUGCCAGGAGUGCAAGGUGAAGCCGGCUGGUGAGCUGUGCCGUCCCAAGAAGGACAUGUGUGACCUCGAGGAGUUCUGUGACGGCCGGCACCCUGAGUGCCCGGAAGACGCCUUCCAGGAGAACGGCACGCCCUGCUCCGGGGGCUACUGCUACAACGGGGCCUGUCCCACACUGGCCCAGCAGUGCCAGGCCUUCUGGGGGCCAGGUGGGCAGGCUGCCGAGGAGUCCUGCUUCUCCUAUGACAUCCUACCAGGCUGCAAGGCCAGCCGGUACAGGGCUGACAUGUGUGGCGUUCUGCAGUGCAAGGGUGGGCAGCAGCCCCUGGGGCGUGCCAUCUGCAUCGUGGAUGUGUGCCACGCGCUCACCACAGAGGAUGGCACUGCGUAUGAACCAGUGCCCGAGGGCACCCGGUGUGGACCAGAGAAGGUUUGCUGGAAAGGACGUUGCCAGGACUUACACGUUUACAGAUCCAGCAACUGCUCUGCCCAGUGCCACAACCAUGGGGUGUGCAACCACAAGCAGGAGUGCCACUGCCACGCGGGCUGGGCCCCGCCCCACUGCGCGAAGCUGCUGACUGAGGUGCACGCAGCGUCCGGGAGCCUCCCCGUCUUCGUGGUGGUGGUUCUGGUGCUCCUGGCAGUUGUGCUGGUCACCCUGGCAGGCAUCAUCGUCUACCGCAAAGCCCGGAGCCGCAUCCUGAGCAGGAACGUGGCUCCCAAGACCACAAUGGGGCGCUCCAACCCCCUGUUCCACCAGGCUGCCAGCCGCGUGCCGGCCAAGGGCGGGGCUCCAGCCCCAUCCAGGGGCCCCCAAGAGCUGGUCCCCACCACCCACCCGGGCCAGCCCGCCCGACACCCGGCCUCCUCGGUGGCUCUGAAGAGGCCGCCCCCUGCUCCUCCGGUCACUGUGUCCAGCCCACCCUUCCCAGUUCCUGUCUACACCCGGCAGGCACCAAAGCAGGUCAUCAAGCCAACGUUCGCACCCCCAGUGCCCCCAGUCAAACCCGGGGCUGGUGCGGCCAACCCUGGUCCAGCUGAGGGUGCUGUUGGCCCAAAGGUUGCCCUGAAGCCCCCCAUCCAGAGGAAGCAAGGAGCCGGAGCUCCCACAGCACCCUAGGGGGGCACCUGCGCCUGUGUGGAAAUUUGGAGAAGUUGCGGCAGAGAAGCCAUGCGUUCCAGCAUUCCACGGUCCAGCUAGUGCCGCUCAGCCCUAGACCCUGACUUUGCAGGCUCAGCUGCUGUUCUAACCUCAGGAAUGCAUCUACCUGAGAGGCUCCUGCUGUCCACGCCCUCAGCCAAUUCCUUCUCCCCGCCUUGGCCACGUGUAGCCCCAGCUGUCUGCAGGCACCAGGCUGGGAUGAGCUGUGUGCUUGCGGGUGCGUGUGUGUGUACGUGUCUCCAGGUGGCCGCUGGUCUCCCGCUGUGUUCAGGAGGCCACAUAUACAGCCCCUCCCAGCCACACCUGCCCCUGCUCUGGGGCCUGCUGAGCCGGCUGCCCUGGGCACCCGGUUCCAGGCAGCACAGACGUGGGGCAUCCCCAGAAAGACUCCAUCCCAGGACCAGGUUCCCCUGCGUGCUCUUCGAGAGGGUGUCAGUGAGCAGACUGCACCCCAAGCUCCCGACUCCAGGUCCCCUGAUCUUGGGGCCUGUUUCCCAUGGGAUUCAAGAGGGACAGCCCCAGCUUUGUGUGUGUUUAAGCUUAGGAAUCGCCUUUAUGGAAAGGGCUAUGUGGGAGAGUCAGCUAUCUUGUCUGGUUUUCUUGAGACCUCAGAUGUGUGUUCAGCAGGGCUGAAAGCUUUUAUUCUUUAAUAAUGAGAAAUGUAUAUUUUACUAAUAAAUUAUUGACCGAG